GAACAACCAGGAAGCGGCUGGGUUGAGAGCUGUCCCCGGUUCUCCGUUCUGCUCUCGGGGGCACCUUCCGGGGUUCCUAAGCCGCGGGGCCCCUCGCUGCCCCUCGAGGCCCUUUCCCUGACCUAGGCUUUGGCCUGGGCUACUCGUUCCGGAGCCGCCAUGUCGUCCGACUUCGAAGGUUACGAGCAGGACUUCGCGGUGCUCACUGCAGAGAUCACCAGCAAGAUUGCGAGGGUCCCACGACUCCCGCCUGAUGAAAAGAAACAGAUGGUUGCAAAUGUGGAGAAACAGCUUGAAGAAGCGAAAGAACUGCUUGAACAGAUGGAUUUGGAAGUCCGAGAGAUACCACCCCAAAGUCGAGGGAUGUACAGCAACAGAAUGAGAAGCUACAAACAAGAAAUGGGAAAACUCGAAACAGAUUUUAAAAGGUCACGGAUCGCCUACAGUGACGAAGUACGGAAUGAGCUCCUGGGGGAUGAUGGGAAUUCCUCAGAGAACCAGUUGAUAAAAUUACGUGAAGAGAGGGCACAUCUGCUCGAUAACACAGAGAGGCUGGAAAGGUCAUCUCGGAGACUAGAGGCUGGAUACCAAAUAGCAGUGGAAACCGAGCAAAUUGGUCAGGAGAUGUUGGAAAACCUUAGUCAUGACAGAGAAAAGAUACAGCGAGCACGUGAAAGACUUCGGGAAACAGAUGCUAAUUUGGGAAAAAGCUCCAGGAUUCUGACAGGGAUGUUGCGAAGGUAAGAGCAAGAAUCAUCCAGAACCGCAUCCUGCUCGUCAUCCUAGGGAUCAUCGUGGUCAUCACCAUCCUGAUGGCGAUCACUUUUUCUGUCAGAAGACACUGAUGUAUCUGCUCUCCCUUGAUAAACAGCAACAACAGCUUGUUCUGAGUAAUUAAGACAAAAUGGUCACAUGAAUCAUUCUGUUGCGCUGACAGGCCCCAGGUGACCCUCUCUCUCCCUCACCGCCGUUGGGCUGAAGUGCAAAGAGUGUAAAAAUAUUUUCUAUUCCUGUUUGCAUGUGGGUUGGUUUCCUUUUCGAGGUUUGUCUUCACCCAGAUUCGUUUUUUAGAGGGGAAGGUGAAUGUUUAUUUACCUUUUUGCUAAUGUCAUCAACUAGCCAAAAUAGCCCCAGUGACACUCCUAGCCCUCUGGACGUGUCAAGGGCCGUGGUUUGGGAGAGGACAUGAUGAGUCAGUCACGAGAGCUUCUGUUUGUCACCCGCCUCUUGUUGCUGAAAAGCUCUUCUGUGAUGUCUGAGGAUAAAAAUGCAGCAAAAAGCAGGGGAUGGAGUCAGUGACCCCGUCCAGCAAGCCAGCCCUGUUCCUACACAGGCCUCAUGAAUAUAGUCAUCAACCUGCCUGAGUGCUUUCAUUGUAAAGGUCGGUAUUUAAUGUCGGUUGUACAGGAAAUUGACUUAGCACUUUCCCUGUUUUUCUAUUGCAUAAUUUUUUUUUUAACCCAAAGAUAUUUUUUUUGCUGAGCCUGCCCAGUAUUCACUGUUCACAACUUUGAUUACUGGCUACAAGAAAUAUUUUCUUGCCUUCCCCAAAUCCCAUACUCCCCAGAAUCUGCUGGCAAAGUGAGCCCUGGUACAGGAUUUAAUUGUGACCUCGUCUUCCCUGACCUGUGUAAGCAUCUCUGUAUCCUUUCGGUUUUAAUAUCUGCACUGCCAAAAGCAGUCCUCAUACUUGCAAAAGGUCUGACAAGGUUCUCUCCACAUACAUUCCAGUAUGUAAAGAGACCAUGAAUAUUUCAGUAAGAGCAAGAACAUGACUCCAUCAGUGUGAAAUUUCAAAUGUGAUUAUAAAUAUGGGAGAGUCCUAUAGGAGGGUCCACCAGAGAUAAACUUCACGGAAAACGUUCCCUAACCUCCUUUAAAAGAAUAGAGGAUGGCAGAUUGUUCCAAAAGGAAUGGCUUGGGUUUUUAACUAACAAAUGUUAGCAAGCCUUUCUUGAAUUCACUAUGUAUUCAAACUUCUAAUAUGCUUUGUGAUUUUUUUCUUUCAUUUCUUUCUGUCUGAGGUAACCAGGAAUUGCGUUCAAAAUGAGCUCAUUUGUGAUCAGGCUUAAAAGUUGCCCAAGCUGAGGUCGUUUCCCCCCAGUCACAAAGCAGAAUGUUUUUCUCAAGACUUCAUAGGCACUUACUGGUCCGUACUAUCUUUGGAAUAUAAUUAGAAGCUUUGAAUCCUUGAAAAGCAAACCUGUUCUCUUCAUCAAAAAUGCUAACCACCUGUGCCCGUGGAUCAAUAUCACCUGGAUGUAGUGCUUGAUAUUUUUCCCAACUCAGAAGAAAACCAUUAUGGUUUAGAGAGGAAAUGCAGAAUGGCAGAAUCCACCAGAGAAAUUGCACUUAUCGAAACAGGCCAAGGCCUGCAUGUGUUCGGAUAAAUCAUUUAGUAUUGUGUAAAUAAAGCUGCAGCCUUUACUUCGGAGGGAUGGUGUGGGAUUUUGGCCGAGGGAAGCAGGACAGAGAAGGAGCAGGAAGCUAUGCUAAUUUUCCUGUCAGCUUAAGGGAUCCGUCUCAGCAAGAAUCUUGUAUUCUGAUAACGGAAUGCUGUACGUGCUGACCACAUCUAAGAACCAUUAAAAAGCAAGGAAACAAACAAACAACCCUUUUCUCAUUCCGACACACGAAUAGUCAUCGAGUAUUACACCAGCCCCUCUGGUGGCUUCCUUCAAAACUGUUGAUCUUAGCUAAAGUGUAUAACCAGUUACCAGCUGCACUUCGCACGGCCAUCCCGUCCACAAUGCAGCAGACUCUUCCCAAGGCCACCUAGCAAGCAAGGUUGAUCGGAUCAUCUAAACUGGCCGCCUCCUGAAUAUUUCACUGAAUCCUGGCGUUCAUGUUGAAGCAGACAAAAUGAGAAAGGAGGAGGGCAUUGCUCACCUCUCAAUAGCUUUUUUCGUUCAAGUUCUAUGUCUUUAUCAGCUCUUGCCUGUGAUUUUACCCCAAUUCAACCUUGGGAGUGGGAAGAAUAUGAACAGAUAACCCUUGGCCUAACAGCUCCAUCAAACCUCCUUGAGAGCAACUACCUAGGCCAGGCUAGUGAGUGCUUUGUGAGGAAGCUGGUCAGAAGGUUCCCUCAACUCCUUCCUGGUCCUCCUGGACACUGCAGAAAAGACUUAGGGGAUCCCCAGCAGAGGCCAAUUGCUCUCCUUCCUUCCCUGCCCCACCAGGAAAGGAAUAACGUCCACAGACUUGAAGCAGAUAGUGAAGUAGAUCUGUGAGAGGUUCUAGGUACUUAGUGUGUAGACUUUGACGAAUAUUUCUCAAGUUGGGAGCCCUUGUUAAAAAUGAUGUUUAAGGGAGUGGUUGGGGGGAAGAUGAAGGCAUGGAGGAGGAAGAAGAGAAGGAAGCCCUUGCCAUAUAAAAUUCAUGCAGACUAAACAGUUUCCCUGACAGAAUAAAUAAAGUGGAUGCUACCCCACUCCAGAAUCAAAAGCAAUUUAAUUAAAGUCUCUUAAGUUGUAAAGAGUUUUAAAUGAUCCGUGUUGAAGGCGAAUGCCUGCAAAUGCAGUGGGUCUGACGUCAGCUGCCGGGCCUGGGCUGGGAGGCCAUUUGCUAUUCUGUUUAAGGCAGGCUGGAUUGUCUUAUUUUGGAACCAGCUUGGUGGGGGGUUUGCUUUGCUACUGCUUCUGAGCCCUGAGCUUCAAAGGCUGAAAUUAAUGGUGAACAAAAUUGUGCGGCUCUGGCCAUCCCAUGCGGGGCAAGCCCAUUGAGGGUUAUCAUUAAGUAAAGAAAUAAAGAGGGGGAAAAAAGCCUGCCUGUUCCAAAAACCUCAUCAGAUAAUGACCUCAGUGAUUGGGUUUUCAUUACCAAACAGCAUCCAGAGAUUAUCAACCCAUAGAAGAAGGGAGGGGAAAAAAAAGAAAGAAAGGAAAAGCAACUGUCUUUCUCUCCCUCUCUUUCUCCUUUUUUUUUGCACAUCUUUUCUUUAAAACUGUCAGAUCAUUUCAGUAUUUCAAAUCCGAGGAAAACAGCCUGCCUGCUGCUGUAUUUGAAGUUGUAAUGGUGUCAAAAAGUCACGACUGACUGACAGCCGUCAGUCCCAGAGGGGCUCAUUAAAUCAUAAAAACUUGACAAGGAAAUAAUUGCGCAUUGCCAGCAACUUGGCGCCUGUUUAGACGUUUUUAUUUUCUUUCAUUAUUAGUCCCCACCAUUACGUUCAUUAACAAAUUGCAUUAAACAACUGUUAAGGGCUAA